CCUUUGUCCUCACAGGUCGCGGAGAGGCGGACCCCCUCCUUGGAAGCCCCUUCCCACGCGGAUUGCUGAGGAAGCCUUUGUGGGUUCGUCGGGUUUCCAAAUCUCUGGUCAGCCAGGCCUCUCUCAGAUCAGGGUCAAAACUUGAGAGGGUUUCAGCUUUUUCUUUAGUUAGUUUGUUUUCAUUGUUGAAUGUUUUUCCAGAUUGUUAGUAUUUGCCUUCUCUAGACCGGCAAUCUACUUGGGUGCAAGCCUGGGCCCCGAAACGUGGAUGCUUAAAACCCAUUUCUACCUUUAUUUUCUCAAGUAGUUGAACGAUUGAGAUUCUCGAGGUUACUCAUGAGGUUCUGCCCCAGUUAAUUCACCGCCUGGAUGAAUUAUUUGGGGUGUACGGCGGUCUGCAUGCUCCUCCCCCAGUUCAGUGGCCAAAUUUGAGGAGAAUGAGGGAUCUCUUCUCCACAUUUCCAACAUUGUUUGCCAGUUGCUGCUUAGGUGACAUGGAUCAGCAACGAAGCGUCGGUUUCAGUGGUUUCUUUUUCUGGACUCCGGUAAUUCACUGCUGCUGAAUCUUUUUCAAGAUUUUGCUCUCUUUAAAAUGAGUGGUGUGAUGGCAUAUUUGUGGUCCACAUGGAAUCGCGAGGUGCCAUCCGAAGUUAGGAUUCAAAUUUAGGACUUUAAGCUCUCUUUUCCUCAGGUAUUUGUGGAUGGGAAUCUCCAUGGAUUGCUCAGAGUGCUGCCACUGUCCCUUGUGCGUGAUGCUUUGUGUGUGGUCUCGUGGGAUGUAGUUACAGUAGCCGCCCAGACUGUGAAUGAAGUGUGGGAACCAGGGCCUCAUUCACAGCUGGAAAGCAGGAGGAGGCCGCAGGACAUUGGCAGGUGCUCCUCUCCCUGUUCCGUGGUGCUGGGGCCCCUUGCUUAUGUGGGUGGCUCUUGGUCCCUGGGAUUUGUGAAUGGAGUCUGCAGGCCCCAGUGUUGUCUGGAAUAUUCUUUAGUUCAGAUUGGAGGCUAGCAAUGACUGCCAGGCUUGGCCUUGCCGCCACUGGGCGCUAUUUAUCACUCUCCCUAUCUUCCUGGAGCUUAGCCGAGUCUUCCUGGAGCUGAGAGGUGCCUAAUUGUUUGUGGUUUUUCUGAUUGAACUUGUUUGGUGCCUCUAGGCAAAAAUUCCUUUGGCUCCUUCUAGUAUUUUCAGGGUCUUGAAGGCCCAUAUUCCUGAGCAUGAGGAAUCUAAGUCUGUUAUUUUUUCCUAAAUUUUCAUGUUAAAUACCACGUUGACAAAGGACAGCUGCUAAUAUUUUGAUCACACAGAUACAGACGGUGCUCCCUGGUUAAGGCCUCCAGGUAGGGGACAGGUAGAGUCAGUGAUGGGGAAGAAGCCUUCUGUAAGUCCCUUUCCUUUGGGUAGACAGUAGAUUACCCUUUAGGCUUUAGCAAGAUGUGGGGGUUAGAAGUCUUCUAUUCUUGGAAAAGCCUUUAGUCGUUUUCUUUGGGCUGGGGCCUCUUCUCUUAGGGACUGCUGUCACCCUUUCUCGGUUUCUUUUGAUUACCUUUCAUGGCCCCAGAGGAGUGAUCCCUUCCCUUAUUUAUACCUCUUGGACUUGUCAUCCUGCUACAUUUUGUCAGCAAGUUAAUUCACCUUGUGCAGUUUUGAAAGAUGUCCAGUGGGACACCUCACAAGUCAGCUCCGAUGUCCUCAGGACAAGACUGCUAUAGUCACCAGUGCUUUGUUGCUUUCUGGCGCUCCGGUAGGAUCCAGGCUCACUUGGUAUAUCCCCUGCUGCAGAUUACGGUCCACUUCUCCCGGGAGCUGCUUUCAAGUUGAAGUAUUGAUAACACCAAGGAACUCUAUCACAAUUUGAAAAGAUAAGCAAAAGUUUGAUUUCCAGACACUACAGAAGAAGUAAAAAUGCGUCCAAUGCGAAUUUUUGUGAAUGAUGACCGCCAUGUGAUGGCAAAGCAUUCUUCCGUUUAUCCAACACAAGAGGAGCUGGAGGCAGUCCAGAACAUGGUGUCCCACACGGAGCGGGCGCUCAAAGCUGUGUCCGACUGGAUAGACGAGCAGGAAAAGGGUAGCAGCGAGCAGGCAGAGUCCGAUAACAUGGAUGUGCCCCCAGAGGACGACAGUAAAGAAGGGGCUGGGGAACAGAAGACGGAGCACAUGACCAGAACCCUGCGGGGAGUGAUGCGGGUGGGCCUGGUGGCAAAGGGCCUCCUACUCAAGGGGGACUUGGAUCUGGAGCUGGUGCUGCUGUGUAAGGAGAAGCCCACAACCGCCCUCCUGGACAAGGUGGCCGACAACCUGGCCAUCCAGCUUGCUGCUGUAACAGAAGACAAGUACGAAAUACUGCAAUCUGUCGACGAUGCUGCGAUUGUGAUAAAAAACACAAAAGAGCCUCCAUUGUCCCUGACCAUCCACCUGACAUCCCCUGUUGUCAGAGAAGAAAUGGAGAAAGUAUUAGCUGGAGAAACGCUAUCAGUCAACGACCCCCCGGACGUUCUGGACAGGCAGAAAUGCCUUGCUGCCUUGGCGUCCCUCCGACACGCCAAGUGGUUCCAGGCCAGAGCCAACGGGCUGAAGUCUUGUGUCAUUGUGAUCCGGGUCUUGAGGGACCUGUGCACUCGCGUGCCCACCUGGGGUCCCCUCCGAGGCUGGCCUCUCGAGCUCCUGUGUGAGAAAUCCAUUGGCACGGCCAACAGACCGAUGGGUGCUGGCGAGGCCCUGCGGAGAGUGCUGGAGUGCCUGGCGUCGGGCAUCGUGAUGCCAGAUGGUUCUGGCAUUUAUGACCCUUGUGAAAAAGAAGCCACUGAUGCUAUUGGGCAUCUAGACAGACAGCAACGGGAAGAUAUCACACAGAGUGCGCAGCACGCACUGCGGCUCGCUGCCUUCGGCCAGCUCCAUAAAGUCCUAGGCAUGGACCCUCUGCCUUCCAAGAUGCCCAAGAAACCAAAGAAUGAAAACCCAGUGGACUACACCGUUCAGAUCCCACCAAGCACCACCUAUGCCAUUACGCCCAUGAAACGCCCAAUGGAGGAGGACGGGGAGGAGAAGUCGCCCAGCAAAAAGAAGAAGAAGAUUCAGAAGAAAGAGGAGAAGGCAGAGCCCCCCCAGGCUAUGAAUGCCCUGAUGCGGUUGAACCAGCUGAAGCCAGGGCUGCAGUACAAGCUGGUGUCCCAGACUGGGCCCGUCCAUGCCCCCAUCUUUACCAUGUCUGUGGAGGUUGAUGGCAAUUCAUUCGAGGCCUCUGGGCCCUCCAAAAAGACGGCCAAGCUGCACGUGGCCGUUAAGGUGUUACAGGACAUGGGCUUGCCGACGGGUGCUGAAGGCAGGGACUCGAGCAAGGGGGAGGACUCGGCUGAGGAGACCGAGGCGAAGCCAGCAGUGGUGGCCCCUGCCCCAGUGGUAGAAGCUGUCUCCACCCCUAGUGCGGCCUUUCCCUCAGAUGCCACUGCCGAGAACGUAAAACAGCAGGGGCCGAUCCUGACAAAGCACGGCAAGAACCCAGUCAUGGAGCUGAACGAGAAGAGGCGUGGGCUCAAGUACGAGCUCAUCUCCGAGACCGGGGGCAGCCACGACAAGCGCUUCGUCAUGGAGGUCGAAGUGGAUGGACAGAAGUUCCAAGGUGCUGGUUCCAACAAAAAGGUGGCGAAGGCCUACGCUGCUCUUGCUGCCCUAGAAAAGCUUUUCCCUGACACCCCUCUCGCCCUUGAUGCCAACAAAAAGAAGAGAGCCCCAGUACCCGUCAGAGGGGGACCGAAAUUUGCUGCUAAGCCACAUAACCCUGGCUUCGGCAUGGGAGGCCCCAUGCACAACGAAGUGCCCCCACCCCCCAACCUUCGAGGGCGGGGAAGAGGCGGGAGCAUCCGGGGACGAGGGCGCGGGCGAGGAUUUGGUGGCGCCAACCAUGGAGGCUACAUGAAUGCCGGUGCUGGGUAUGGAAGCUAUGGGUACGGAGGCAACUCGGCGACAGCAGGCUACAGUCAGUUCUACAGCAACGGAGGGCAUUCUGGGAAUGCCAGUGGCGGUGGCGGCGGGGGCGGUGGUGGCUCCUCCGGCUAUGGCUCCUACUACCAAGGUGACAACUACAACUCACCGGUGCCCCCAAAACACGCUGGGAAGAAGCAGCCGCACGGGGGCCAGCAGAAGCCCUCCUACGGCUCGGGCUACCAGUCCCACCAGGGCCAGCAGCAGUCCUACAACCAGAGCCCCUACAGCAACUAUGGCCCUCCACAGGGCAAGCAGAAAGGCUAUAACCAUGGACAAGGCAGCUACUCCUACUCGAACUCCUACAACUCUCCCGGGGGCGGGGGCGGAUCCGACUACAACUACGAGAGCAAAUUCAACUACAGUGGUAGUGGAGGCCGAAGCGGCGGGAACAGCUACGGCUCAGGCGGGGCAUCCUACAACCCAGGGUCACACGGGGGCUACGGCGGAGGUUCUGGGGGCGGCUCCUCAUACCAAGGCAAACAAGGAGGCUACUCACAGUCGAACUACAACUCCCCGGGGUCCGGCCAGAACUACAGUGGCCCUCCCAGCUCCUACCAGUCCUCACAAGGCGGCUAUGGCAGAAACGCAGACCACAGCAUGAACUACCAGUACAGAUAAGCCCCCGCGGGGCGGAGAUUUCUACCUUCUGCACUUACUCCCCAUCAGAAGAUCGAGUUUUAUGCAUCACAGUUAACAUGUCAGCUGGCCCUCCAGGCCCCCGCCCCCAUCCCGUCCACGUUGCUGUGUCGUGAGGUGCAGCGGGUCACCCUGUGGCCCGUCCUGUGACCCAUAUUUAGCCGUGUUUGGGACUCCGUGUCUUCAAUGGUUUGUUAGUUGCCAUUACAACUUUGUCUGGGUAGAGUUUUUGAGUUUUUGCAGUUCAGUAUCCCUCUGUCUAUUCACACUUCGUGUUAGUGGUAACUCAGUUUGUCUUUAAAUAGUUACAGAAGGGAUACGUCAUUUGUUAAUGCUUUUGUGAAGUGAGUUAAACGAGCUUUCUGUAUUUUAAUGCUUUAGUGUUUCAGUUUUAUAAGUGAAGAUUUUAUUUUAAAAACCAGUGGGAAAGAGUGGGGGGUUUCUUUUUAUGUCUGGGUCAUUCAGGCAGUACAUCUGAAUUAAGCUGAAUGUAGACAAAUAAAGAAAAACAAAACUGCGCCCGUCUUAGGCCUGGGUGUCUGACCCACCAGCAGUGCAAUGGGCAGGUUUCCCCACUCUAUUCCUGCUCUUGGGAAAGCAGCGUGGGCCAUCAGGAUGGUCCCUGGUCCUUAGAGAGGGUCCAGUUCAGGCUUCUAGACAUUUUACUCAUGCUCAGCGAAGGCUGGUUCCUGGUCCCCUGGGCUGUGUAGACCCGGUGUCCCACCAGGCUCCAGGCUCCCACCAUCUACAGAGGGGCUUACAGCGCCCAUUCUGGUCUUGGGGAACCCAUCACAAAAUAGGCUUUUUCUGCUCCCCGAUUCUGGUGUAGUUCUAAGUACACAGUGAUGUCCUCUGUAGGGGCGUGCCUGUGGUGGAACAUAACGCAGUUACAAAAGAAAGGGCAGGUGAGGCCUGGGUAACCCCAGCCAUGGACCGUCAGUGGCUGGAGGGAGCUUCGUGUCUGUGCUGGAGCUGCAGCCUGCUCGCCAUCUGGAGGCUCAGUGGAGUGGGGAGUUGGGGUUCUCAUACCAGCAGAUUUCCCUAGAGCGUGAUUCUCCCAUCUGAGGCAAUCUUGCCUCCCAGGGGAAAUUUUGCAAUGUUUGGAGGAUGUUGUCACAGCUAGUAGCGGGUGCUCUGGGAUCUGGUGGAUAGAUGCCAAGGAUGCUGUCAAGCAUACUGUACUGCCCAGAACAGUGGCCCAUAGCAGGGACCUGCCCUAUCAAAAUAUCAGGUGUAUGGAGGUGGAGUCCCAACGCUAGAGCAGCCCUUCUCAGCUCCACCCUGCCCGGGGAGGGAGGAGGAGCUCUGGUUUCAGAGCAGUGCCGGGAUUGCCUUUCCCCAGGAUCUGUGUCGGCCAUCCAGGAAGAACUGUACUGGCCAAGCCUGGGACCACACGUCUGCAGAGAUCCUGCUCUGCUGGCCUGAGCCCCAGGCCUUGGCCUCCUGUGCUUGGGUAACCAUGGCCACUGGGAAAAGCAAGGACCGUGUUUGACUUUCUUGGAGAGGUGAAAGAGGUGAAAGAACAAGUUGUGUGCUAGAAAACUUUUGAGGAAUUCUUAUUUGUGUUAGAGCAGAGGAGGUCCCAGAUACCAAGUGGCGCCUCCCAGGAAAGGCUGGGAGAAGAGGUGGCCUGGAGUACCCCGAGAUCCCAGCAGCGCACACAGUGGAGGGAUGAGGAUGGAUGGGUCCUAACCCCUGAUUUUGAUGGGAUGUGUUCAUGUCCUAUCUCCUCUCCUGGACACAUUAAGGGGUUGGGACAAGAAGAGACUCCUGUGAGAUCAGCAGACCUCGUGUUUAAGGAGAGAAUGCCUGCCUGCAACACUCAUGGAGAGGGACACUUCCUGGCCCCACCUGCUAAAUACCUCCAAACUCUGGGCAGGCGCCUGCAUUCUCAACACAGGACUUCCCUUAACAGUUUCCGGAUCAGUGACCACCACCACGUUCAGGUUUCUGAAUGCAGACCCACCACGAGGGAUGGAUUCCACCCGCCCGCCCUGCUGCAGAUACAUGCGGCACAGCAGGCACGUGCCUGGAGAGAACAGCUCCUGAGCACAGCACCCUUGGAGCCCUCACCCCGCUCACGAUCCUCACCAGUGCUGAUGAUGCCGUCAUGCUGCUGGCCUGAGACAGUAUCCCAGCUACAACAGGACGACACCGGGUUCAGGAAUAUGUGGCUAUCACCUUGAGCACUGACAGUGGCCUUCCAGGCUAGUUGCCUUCCAAACGCAGGUAGCCGACCUGCAGGAGGGCCUACAAACGGGCCCAGCAAGAGCUGGGCAACAGCUGGCUUGUGAAAUGAGACACCUUGACCAAUAUGCUUUGGGUGGACGGUCUCCUACAUGUUCAGUGGAGGCCACCAGGAGCAUCCAUGAGCGGGGAAGGGGUCCACACCCUUACAUGGCAAGUUGAUACGAUGGGGUGCUUGGUGGAUGGGCCAUGGAGGUCCGUGAGCUGGAACUGGGCACACGCCAUCCCAGAGGGCUCAGGAUGCCCCAGGAAGGAAAGAAGGGCAACAGACUACACGAUUGGACGUGUGUGGUUGACUGGGAUGAAGUUGGAGGGAGGGGCAGGGCCUUGCAGGGGAUUGGUACUGAUCCCAGGGAGGAAGUGUUGGGGCUUCAUGAACUAGGAUGAAAGGAGGCCCCUGAGCCAUGACAAGGGGCACAUCCAGGAUUUCCGCCACCCUGAAUUUAGUAGAGCUAGUAGGCCCUGGUCGUCACUCUGGGCAGGGAUGCCGUCAGCCUUGAGGGUCGCCACCCACCUGUGUGUUGCCCUCUGUCCUGGCAGGGAAACAUACACCCCUUGUCUCACCACCAACCUUGCUUGUGUAGUCAGCAGGGCUGGCCCUGCCCCAAGGACUCACUGCAUGUACCCGGACCCCUAGGCCUGGCCUUUGCAGCAUAGUUGGGAGCUUCUGGAUUCCAUCUGCACCUGUGAGCCCCAUGCUGGCUGUGCACUGCGCGGGCCUGAGACUGCUGGAUACAAUGUUGGGCAACAACUCAGCCAGCCUGAUGGCAGCCUCAGAGGCUUACUCUAACCCAUCCCAGAAUAAAUGGAGACUUCAUGUGUU